AUGAUGGCACGUCGGGACCCCACAUCUUGGGCCAAGAGACUGGUGAGAGCCCAGACCCUCCAGAAGCAGCGGAGGGCCCCAGUUGGGCCAAGGGCUCCCCCGCCCGAUGAAGAAGAUCCCAGGCUCAAGUGCAAAAACUGCGGGGCCUUUGGCCACACGGCCAGAAGUACCAGGUGCCCCAUGAAGUGCUGGAAGGCAGCCCUGGUUCCAGCGACCUUGGGGAAAAAGGAAGGGAAGGAAAACCUGAAACCAUGGAAGCCCCGGGUUGAAGCCAACCCGGGGCCCUUGAACAAGGAUAAGGGAGAGAAGGAAGAGAGACCAAGGCAACAAGACCCGCAGAGGAAGGCUCUCCUCCACAUGUUUUCCGGGAAACCUCCAGAGAAGCCGCUGCCGAAUGGAAAAGGAUCCACGGAACCUUCUGAUUAUCUGAGGGUUGCAAGCGGGCCAAUGCCGGUCCACACAACCAGUAAGAGGCCGCGCUUGGACCCUGUCCUCGCUGAUCGCUCAGCUACCGAAAUGUCUGGCAGGGGCUCCGUCUUGGCUUCACUGUCUCCCCUCAGAAAAGCCAGCCUGAGCUCCUCCUCAAGUCUUGGACCAAAGGAAAGACAGACAGGGGCUGCGGCCGACAUGCCUCAGCCUGCAGUCAGGCACCAGGGCCGCGAGCCUCUCCUCGUGGUGAAGCCGACACACAGCCGCCCCGAGGGUGGCUGCCGAGAAGUUCCCCAGGCUGCCUCCAAAACCCACGGCCUGCUCCAGGCCGCCAGACCCCAGGCACAAGACAAACGUCCUGCGGUGACCUCACAGCCCUGCCCGCCAGCCGCCACACACAGCUUGGGCCUAGGCUCCAAUCUCAGCUUCGGGCCAGGAGCCAAGAGACCUGCCCAGGCUCCGAUUCAGGCUUGCCUGAACUUCCCCAAGAAACCGAGACUGGGUCCCUUCCAGAUCCCCGAAAGCGCCAUCCAGGGAGGUGAGCUGGGGGCCCCGGAGAAUCUCCAACCUCCGCCAGCCGCAACCGAACUUGGACCAAGUACGUCGCCCCAGAUGGGCAGGAGGACACCGGCCCAGGUGCCCAGCGUCGACCGGCAGCCUCCGCACAGCAGACCUUGCCUGCCCACUGCCCAGGCCUGCACCAUGUCCCAUCACCCAGCGGCCAGCCAUGAUGGGGCCCAGCCUCUCAGAGUGCUCUUCCGGAGACUGGAAAACGGACGCUGGAGCUCCAGCCUCCUGGCGGCCCCCUCAUUUCACUCUCCUGAGAAGCCGGGAGCCUUCCUCGCUCAGAGCCCUCAUGUGUCAGAGAAGUCUGAGGCUCCCUGUGUUCGUGUCCCACCGAGCGUCCUCUAUGAGGACCUUCAGGUUUCCUCCUCCUCAGAGGACAGCGAUUCUGACCUGGAGUGA